ACUGCCUCCCGCCGCCUCCUGCCCGCGCCAUGACCCAGCCGGUGCCCCGGCUCUCCGUGCCCGCCGCGCUGGCCCUGGGCUCAGCCGCACUGGGCGCCGCCUUCGCCACUGGCCUCUUCCUGGGGAGGCGGUGCCCCCCAUGGCGAGGCCGGCGAGAGCAGUGCCUGCUUCCCCCCGAGGACAGCCGCCUGUGGCAGUAUCUUCUGAGCCGCUCCAUGCGGGAGCACCCGGCGCUGCGAAGCCUGAGGCUGCUGACCCUGGAGCAGCCGCAGGGGGAUUCUAUGAUGACCUGCGAGCAGGCCCAGCUCUUGGCCAACCUGGCGCGGCUCAUCCAGGCCAAGAAGGCGCUGGACCUGGGCACCUUCACGGGCUACUCCGCCCUGGCCCUGGCCCUGGCGCUGCCCGCGGACGGGCGCGUGGUGACCUGCGAGGUGGACGCGCAGCCCCCGGAGCUGGGACGGCCCCUGUGGAGGCAGGCCGAGGCGGAGCACAAGAUCGACCUCCGGCUGAAGCCCGCCUUGGAGACCCUGGACGAGCUGCUGGCGGCGGGCGAGGCCGGCACCUUCGACGUGGCCGUGGUGGAUGCGGACAAGGAGAACUGCUCCGCCUACUACGAGCGCUGCCUGCAGCUGCUGCGACCCGGAGGCAUCCUCGCCGUCCUCAGAGUCCUGUGGCGCGGGAAGGUGCUGCAACCUCCGAAAGGGGACGUGGCGGCCGAGUGUGUGCGAAACCUAAACGAACGCAUCCGGCGGGACGUCAGGGUCUACAUCAGCCUCCUGCCCCUGGGCGAUGGACUCACCUUGGCCUUCAAGAUCUAGGGCUGGCCCCUAGUGAGUGGGCUCGAGGGAGGGUUGCCUGGGAACCCCAGGAAUUGACCCUGAGUUUUAAAUUCGAAAAUAAAGUGGGGCUGGGACACACGACCUCCUGAGCCUCCGUGUGUGGCGCUGGAUGGGGAAGGGAGGGAAGGCCCAGCACAGACAGCUCCUGCCUUCAGUGAAAGGGGCCUUGAGAUUCGUCCCCUCCCUGGCGCCAGGUCUGUGGCCCAACUGCAGGAACCUCCAGCUGGCAGGAGGCAGGUUAUAAAGUUUUAACUGGCCUGGCCACGUGUAAUGGCCAGAGACCCCAGCACCUCGGGCUUGUCUGCCUCCUACAUCUCUCCCUCAGGGCAGGCGAAGCUCUGGUUCUGAGCAGCUGGGACUGGUAGAGAGCCACGUCUGGUGUCUGACAACAUGAAAGAGGAUUGCAGGGGA